CAUGAAGUGAUUACUGAAUUUAUUCUAAACUUUUUCUUCAUCCAAUAAGAUAUUCAUGUGAUUAUUCUUUUUUAGACUGUUGACGUGGUGAAUUACAUUGAUGGCUUUUCAAAUGUUGAGUGAGCCUUGCAUUCUGGGGAUAAGCCCCACUUGAUCAUGCCAUAUUAUUAAUAUCUUUUAAAUAUAUUUUUGGAUUCAAUUUGAUAAUAUUUUAUAAGAUUUUUGUGUCUGUGCUCUUAAAGGAUAUUGGGUUGACAUUUUCUUAAUUGUAAUGUCUUUGGUUUUAUUGGGUAAUGCCAAUCUCAUAAAAUCAAUUGAGAAGUGUUCCUUCCUCUUCUUUAUCUGGAAGAGAUUAUGUAAAAUUAUUAUUUCUUCCACAAUGUUUGGUAAACUUCAUCAGUGAAACCACUGGGGCCUAGAGAAUUCUUUUUGGAAGGUUUAAACUACAAAUUCAAUUUAAAAGUUAUACAUACAUAUAUAUGAAAUAAAUCAUUGCUUUAACAUAAACUUUUUUCUUCCUGAAUGAAUUUGGUAAUUUUUUUUAAUUUUAAAAAUUAGUGCAUUUUGUCAAAUUUACAAACAGCUUUUCAUAGUACUGUUCCCUUGUUAUCCUCUUAAGGUCUGUGGGGUUAAUAGUGAUGUUUCUUCUCUCAUUUCUGAUGUUUCUAAUUUGCAUCUUAUUUUUCUUGGUCAUCCAGGCUAGAGGUUUAUCAAUUGUGCUGAACUUUUAAAAUAAUCAACUUUUAGUUUCAUUAAUUUUCUCUAUUGUUUUUCUGUUUCCAAUUUAUUUGAGUUCUGGUCUUCUAAUAAUACUUUCCUUCCUUCUACUUACUUUGGGUUUAUUCUGUUCUUUUUCUAGUUUUGUCACUUGCAAGCUUAGAUCCUUGAUUUGAGAUGUUGUUCUUUUCCAAUAUAAGCAUUUAUAAAUUUCUCUAAAUCACCGUUUUAAAUGCCUUCUGCAAAUUUUGAUAUGUUGCAUUUUCUCUUUCAUUUACUUUUCUAAAUUCCUUUGUGGCUUUCCUUUUGGCCCAUGGGUAAUCCAGAAGUAUGUUGGUGUAUUAGUCCGUGCUUGCAUUGUUAUAAAGAAAUGCCUGAGGCCAGGCACGGUGGCUCAUGUCUGUAAUCCUAGCACUUUGAGAGACUGAAGUAGGCAGAUGCUUGAGACUAGCCUCAGCAACAUGGCAAAACCCCGUCUCUACAAAAAAUUAAAAAAUUAGCUGGGUGUGGUGGUGCAUGCUUGUAGUCCCAGAUACUCUGGAGACUAAGGUGGGAGGAUUCUUUGAGCCAGGAAGAUGGAGGUUGCAAUGAGCUGAGAUUGUGCCACUGCACUCCAGCCUGGGUAAUAGAGCAAGACUGUCUGUCACACACAAGAAAAAAAAAAAAAGAAAGAAAGAAGAAAAGAGAAAUACCUGAGACAGGGUAAUUUGUAAAGAAAAGAGGUUUAAUUGACUUAUGGUUCUGUAGGCUGUUCAGGAAACAGCUCUGGCAUCAGCUUCAGAAGAGGCCUCAGGAAGCUUACAAUCAUGGCAGGUGAAGCCAGGAGUGGGAACACCACAUGGUGAGAGCAGGAGCAGGAGUAGGGGGAGGUGCCACACACUUUUAAAUGAGCAGAUCUCACAAGAACUCACUCACUAUUGUGAGGACAGUACCAAGAGGAUGAUGCUAAGCGAUUCAUGAAAAAUCCACCCCCAUGAGCCAAUCACCUCCCACCAGGCCCCACUUCUAACAUUGGGGAUUACAUUUGAAUAUGAGAUUUUGGUGGAGACACACAUCCAAACUUUAUCGGUUGGUUUCCAAAUAUUUGGAGAUUUACUAGAUAUGUUUCUUUUAUUAAUUUUUAACUUAGUUCCAUUAUGGUUCAAGAAGAUUGUCAGGCCUCUGAGCCCAAGCCAAGCCAUCGCAUCCCCUGUGACUUGCACUUAUACGCCCAGAUGGCCUGAAGUAACUGAAGAAUCACAAAAGAAGUGAAAAUGCCCUGCCCCGCCUUAACUGAUGACAUUCCACCACAAAAGAAGUGUAAAUGGCCAGUCCUUGCCUUAAGUGAUGACAUUACCUUGUGAAAGUCCUUUUCCUGGCUCAUCCUGGCUCAAAAAGCUCCCCCACUGAGCACCUUGUGACCCCCACUCCCAUCCGCUAGAGAACAAACCUCCUUUGACUGUAAUUUUCCUUUACCUACCCAAAUCUUAUAAAAUGGCCCCACCCCUAUCUCCCUUCUCUGACUCUCUUUUCGGACUCAGCCCACCUGCACCCAGGUGGUUAAAAGCUUUAUUGCUCACACAAAGCCUAUUUGGUGGUCUCUUCACAUGGACGCGCAUGAAAAAGAUUCUUUGUAUGACUUCAGUUAUUCCAAAUUUGUGAAAGUUUGUUUUAUGGUCCAGAAUAUGGUUUAGCAUGGUGAAUAUUCCAUGUGUGUUUGAAAAAAAAAGUUUUCUACCUUUGUUGGGUAGAGUGUUUUAUAAAGGUAAAUUAUGUCAACUGGACAUAACGUUGUUUGGGUCUCAUCUGUUGGUACUGAUUUUCUGUCUACUUCUAUCAAUUACUGUGAGAGGAAAGUCAAAGUCUCCAACUAUGGUUGUGGAUUUAUCUAGUUCUCAUUUCUGUUUCUGUUUUAAGUUUUUGGAACUUCUCUUAAUAGGUGUGUACAUUUAAGAUUGUUAUGUUUUCUUGAUUAAUUGAACCUUAUCCCAUUAUGCAAUAUCUCUGUUUAUCUUUAGUAGUAUUUCUUGCUUUGAAAUCUACUUUGAUAUUAAUAUAGCCACUACAUUUUUUCUUUCGAUUAGUGUUUGUAUGGUAUCUCUUCUUUCAUCUUAUUACUUCUAUUCCCAUCUAUGUCUUUAUUUUUAAAGUAGGUUUCUUGUAGAUAGUUAGGUCUUAUUUAUUUUUAAUCAAAUUUGACAAACUCGAUGUUUUAAUUGGUGUGCUUAGAUAAUUUAUAUUUAAUGUAAUUAUUGAUAUGUUUGAAUUUAUUUUAUUAUUGAUUUUCUAGUUGUCUCCUCUGUCUUUAAUUCCUCUGUUUUCCCUUUCUAUUGAUGUCUCACUAUGUUUGCUGACUCUUUUUUUCUUUUUUCUGUAUUUUGCUGUCGAACCCAUCAAUUGAUUUCUUAACUUCACACAGUGUAUUUUUUUCACUUCUAAAAUUUCCAUUUCAUUCUUUAAAAAAAUCUUUAAAAAGACUAUUUUUAGAGCAGUUGUGGGUUCACAGACAAAUUGAGUGAAAAGUACAGAGAGUUCCCAUAUGCCCUCUACCCCUACACAUGCACAACCUCCCACACUGUCAACAUCUGGUACCAGAGUGGUACCUUUGUUACGGGUGAUGAACCUAUACUGAAACCUCACUAUCACCCAAAGUCCAUAAUUUACAUAAGGGGUUUAUUCUUGGUGUUGCAGAUUCUGUGGGUUUGAACAAAUCUAUAAUGACAUAUAGCCACCAUUAUAGUAUCAUACAGAAUAGUUUCACUGCUGUAAAAAUUGUCUAUAUUCUGCAUAUUCAUCUCUCCUUCCCUGCUAAACUCUGGCAAUCACUGACUUUUUUACUGUUUCUAUACUUUUGCCUUUUCCAGAAUAUCGCAUAGUAGGAAUCAUACAAUAUAUAAUCCUUUCAGAUUGGCUUCUUUAACUUAAUAACAUGUAUUUAAGUUUCUUCCUUGUAUUUUCAUGCCUUGAUAGCUCAUUCCUUUUAGAACUGAAUAAUGUUCCAUUGUAUGGAUAUACCACAGUGUAUUAGUCAGGGCUCCGUGGAGGGACAGAACUAAUAGGAUAGAUGUAUAUAUGAAGGGGAGUUUAUUAGGGAGUAUUGACUCACAUUAUCACAAGGCAAAGUCACUCAAUAAGCUAUCUACAAGCUGAGGAGCAAGGAAGCCAGUCCAAGUCCCAAAACCUCAAAAGUAGGGAAGCCAACAGUGCAGCCUUGUCUGCAGCUGAAGGUCUGAGAGCCCUUGGCAAAACACUGGUGUAAGUCCAAGAGUCCAAAAGCUGAAGAACUUGGAAUUUAUUGUUUGAGGGCAUGAAGCAUCCAGCAGGGGAGAAAGAUGAAGGCCAGAAGACCGAGCAAGUCUACUUUUCCAUCUUCUCCUGCAUGCCUUUAUAGCUGUACUGGCAGCUGAUUAGAUGGUGCCCACCCAGAUUGAGGGGGGGUCUGCCUCUCCCAGUCCACUGACUCGAAUGUUAAUCUUCUUUGGCAACACCCUCACAGACACACCCAGGAACAAUACUUUGCAUCCUUCAAUUCAAUCAAGUUGACACUCAGUAUUAACCAUUACACACAGUUUAUUUAUUCAUUCACUUACUGAAGGACAGUCUUGGCUGCUUCAAGGUUUUGGCAGUUAUGAAUAAAGUCACUAUGUACAUCCAUGUGCAGGUUUUUGUGUGGACAUAUGUUUUUAACUCAUUUGAAUAAAUGCCAAGGGAUGUGAUUGCUGGAUUGUAUGUUAAAAAUAUGCUUAAUUUUGUAAGAUGGUUCUUUUUUUUUAUAGUUUCUAUUAUUCUGCCAAUAAUUUCUGUUUUUUUCCCUUUGUUCAAGAGUGUUUAUCUUUACUUUGUGGAGCAUAGUUACGAUAGUUGCCUUAAAAUCUGUGCCUGAUUAUUCUACCAUCUUGGUCUUCUCAGUGGUAGCAUUUAUUGACUGUACUUUUCAUGCAAAUUAGUAAACUUUUAUUGGUUCUUUGUACGCUGAGUGAUUUUAGAUUGUAUCCUGGACAUUCUGAGUAUUUAAUUUGGAUGUUUUUCAUUAAAAUCCUCAAGAGAUUUGGAAGAUUGUUUGCUUAUUUGAGUAGGUAAUCACACUGGUUUUGUUCAGACUAUCUGUACUUUAUGAGUGAUACUUCCAAUGUUAUCUCAGUUUUCGGAACCUCUACUUGGCAGCUUUGAGUAUGUUCCAUGCAUGCACAGCUCAGGGUUAAGCCUGGGCCUGUGCUAGGUCAUACACAGAGUUAGGAGAUCCAUUUCUCUAAUCUCUUAUCUCCGGGACUCCCCAUAGUCACCUACCUAUAUGUUUUCUAUUCCUCAUCCUCUGGCUCAAUAGACCGGGGUUCUUUUGGAGUUUUGGCUGCCUGUGUUGCUACCAGGUCCUGUGACCAGGACCAUUUUGGGUGCUAUGUGGAGAUGGAAAAAAGAGAGAGAAAAUUUACCUACUGACUUACUCCAGUACUCUCUGGACCACAGGAGCCCUUUUCUGUUUGUUUAACUAGAAAAACAGAAUUUCUAUUGGGAUUUUAGCCGACCAUGCUACUUUUCACCCUGGCUCUGCUAGGCAAGCUGUGAAAAUGGGGGAGGGAAUGAGAAUGCAAGGAUUCCUUUCUAUGUUCUUCAGCUUAAAGGAUCCCAGCCUUCUUUCUAGACAGAAGGGAUUUAUCUGAAAGUAUUAGCUGUCUGCAGCACCCCCAUCGCAGCUCAUUUGUGUGAUUGCUUUCAGCCAAAGCCUGUGAAAAGAAAGAGGAAAUAAAAUGAGAAACUUAAUCCUGUGCAAAUUGCUGUUUCAGUUUUUGACUUCUCUUCAUAAUCUGACUGCAUUUCUUUACCUUUCAGAGUCCUUAGGUAGUUGUUUUUUGUAUUUUGUCCAGAGUUUUUAGCUGUAAUCAGCAGAAGAGGUAGGCUUUAUUGAAUUCACUCUUGACUGUACUUUCUUUUAUAUUCUUUUUUCACUUCUAUCUGUACUACCUCUCUCAAGAUACAAUGACUGACACUAAUCCUAUCCUUUUAUUCUUUGAAGUAGAAACCAUGACUAUCCCUUUAAAGACCACAUCUGUCACUUCAGGUAUUUUUACUUGUGGCUUUCAUUUGCUGGCUGAGCGGGUAAAGCCUGUUUAGGAGGAAUACAAUUCAAGAACCUCACUUUGAAGCUAACCAUAGCAAACCUAGUUUACCUCUAGAAUGCAGGUGACAGUGUGCAACCACUCCUGUCAUCUGUCUUUUGUAUGCUCUUCAUAAGCAAUCUUCCUCUUCCUUCCCAGUUCAUUUAUUUAGCCUCUGAUUCAUUCUUCUCUUCUCCCACCCCUUUCUCUUCUACCAGCCAGCCUACCAAUACUUAUUCUCUCUGAAAGGAUCUUAUCCUUUACCAGAAGUUCAGUUAUUACCUCUAAGAACCAGUCCCUUCCCUUUUAAAUUUUCUUUUCCCUGAAAGAGUCAGUUUUAUGUAUUAGAAAAAUGAAGGUAUAUGUUUUCCUUUAAAGGGAUUAUAAUCAUUACAGAAAAUUUGAAAGUUUUCAAAAAAUUAAAAAAAAAACCCAGAAUUUCCCAAAACCUGACUAUCCAAAGAGAAGCACUUAAUGUUAUGUGUGUGAUCUUGAGUGAAAAUUUAAAAUUUAUAUUAGAACAUUUUAUAAAUUAUCCAAACUUUUUGUACGAAAAAAACAGAAAAUGUAAAUAAUAAGAAAAAAAAGCACUCAUCAUCCUACCAUCUAGAAGUAAAUACUGGUUUUAGUUCAGAGUAUGUGUACAGAUACGUGUGUGUGUGUUUGUGUGUGUGUUUGCAGGCUGCUUGGUUGGUUUGGGUGGGGAAUAGUUGAGCCUGAUCUGGGAUCACAGCCUUGCUGUGUUGGAGAAAGGGGUCGGGUGGAGUGGGUGUUGGUAUGCAAAGGUUGAUUUAAAUAAAUGGUUUCGAUUUUGGUAUUUGGACAAGGCUUGAAGUGGAAUCUCCUGGUGAACAAAAUUGGGGAAUGGAAAGAAUUUGGUAGUGUUGUGUUUUGUGUCUUCCUGUCCCUUUUCUUCUGAUUUCCCAAAGAGCUCACCCUGUUCUGUAGACUAAAUCUUAGGCCUCUGUGGCAACAAAGACUAUAGGCUAAUGGCUUAGAUGACAAAGAAAACAAGAGUUGGAAAGGGGCUUUCUCUACAUUUCAAUCAGAACAUAGCAGGACUGCAGCACAGUCAGCACUGAAGUGAACUCCACUGCAUCAGUUUUGUAGCAUCAGGGAGUUCUAGAAAACAGUGCCUUGUGUUGGGAACUAGCAUUCUACCAGUAACUAUGAUAUUGGUGGAGCAAGGGUGAAGAGAGGACCAAAGUGGAGGAACAUGAAGGAAAAACAAUGAGCAAGUUAUUAGAAGUAACCCAUGAAGACUCCAAAAAAGAAUUAGGGGUGACUUUACGGGGGAGAGAGGUCCUGGAGUCAAGAGCCUGAGGGUGUGUGUGUAUAAAUAUGUGUCUAUUUAUAUCUAUAUCAAUCGCUAUCUAUAUCUACAUCUAUCUUUCUUCGAAAAUAGGACAUUUUUACAUCUACUAUUGUAUAAUAUUUCUUCCCUUAAUAAUAUAUCUUGAAAAUCUUGUCAUAUCAAAUAUAGAAAUAUUUUAUCAUUUUAAAUGGCUGCAUUAUAUUCCAUUGACUGCAUGAGGAUUCCAUUGUAAUCAUUGUAUGCAUGUAUGUGAGUAUCAAAAUUUAUUUAACCAUUAUCUAGGUUGUUUUCAAGCUAUUAUCAAUUUCUUAUUAGCAGUUCAUUUUAUUAUUAAAAUAAUAAUGUAUUUUUCUCCUUUAAAAAACAACAUUGUUCUGGCUUCUCAUACUUUCAGCCAUAGAAUCCUUAGAUGGCAUUUAAAAGUUUCUGACUUAUUCUUUCUCAUCUUUUCUGCAUAACCACAUUUAAUCUGUUUUCAAUUUGAUAUACAUGGCCAGCGGUACUGCCCCAAAGGGAAGAGGCAAAAUGGACCCUAAUAGUGCCCACAUGUUGCUCACCUUCUUUCCUGCCCAUCUCAAGGCUCACUGUCUGGCAAGGAUCUGUUAGACUUACAUAUUCUGAAAUAUAAAUGUUGUAAAACUGAGUGGCCUGGCAUGGUGGCUAACAUCUGUAAUCCCAGCACUUUGGGAGGGUGAGGCAGGUGGAUCACCUGAGGUCAGGAGUUUGAGACCAGCCAGGCCAACGUGGUGAAACUCCGUCUCUACUAAAAAUACAAAAAUUAGGCCGGGCACAGUGGCUCACACCUGUAAUCCCAGAACUUUGGGAGGCCGAGGCGAGCAGAUCACGAGUUCAGGAGUUCGAGACCAGCCUGACCAACAUGGUGAAACCCCGUCUGUACUAAAAAUACAAAAAUUAGCCAGGCAUGGUGGCGGGUGCCUGUAAUCCCAGCUACUCAGGAGGCUGAGGCAGGAGAAUCACUUGAACCCAGGGAGGCGAAGGUUGCAGUGAGUUGAGAUUGCAUCACUGCACUCCAGCCUGGACGACAAAGCGAGACUCUGUCUCAAAAAAAAAAAAAAAACAAAAACAAAAACGAAAAACCAAAAACCGAAAACCAAACAAACAAAAAAACCCGAGUGGAUUAGAUUUCUCAGGGACAUUUUCAUUUUAAAGGCAACAAAGAAGUUUUAGAAGCAAAUGAUUGAAAUUCUUAGUUUACCAGGCUGUUACUCAAAAUUCACUCUCCAGCCCUGCUUUGGAGCAGUUGGGAACUUCAGCAUUUUGAUCCACCUUUUUGGAGCCACCUCAUGUGAAAGAUGGAUGAGACCUUCGUCAGCAAACCUGAUUGUGAAGAUGGAAAGGGUCCAACCCCUGGAAGAGAAUGUGGGAAAUGCAGCCAGGCCAAGAUUCGAGAGGAACAAGCUAUUGCUGGUGGCCUCUGUAAUUCAGGGACUGGGGCUGCUCCUGUGCUUCACCUACAUCUGCCUGCACUUCUCUGCUCUUCAGGUAUCACAUCGGUAUCCUCGAAUUCAAAGUAUCAAAGUACAAUUUACCGAAUAUAAGAAGGAGAAAGGUUUCAUCCUCACUUCCCAAAAGGAGGAUGAAAUCAUGAAGGUGCAGAACAACUCAGUCAUCAUCAACUGUGAUGGGUUUUAUCUCAUCUCCCUGAAGGGCUACUUCUCCCAGGAAGUCAACAUUAGCCUUCAUUACCAGAAGGAUGAGGAGCCCCUCUUCCAACUGAAGAAGGUCAGGUCUGUCAACUCCUUGAUGGUGGCCUCUCUGACUUACAAAGACAAAGUCUACUUGAAUGUGACCACUGACAAUACCUCCCUGGAUGACUUCCAUGUGAAUGGCGGAGAACUGAUUCUUAUCCAUCAAAAUCCUGGUGAAUUCUGUGUCCUUUGAGGGGCUGAUGGCAAUAUCUAAAACCAGGCACCAGCAUGAACACCAAGCUGGGGGUGGACAGGGCAUGGAUUCUUCAUUGCAAGUGAAGGAGCCUCCCAGCUCAGCCACGUGGGAUGUGACAAGAAGCAGAUCCUGGCCCUCCCGCCCCCACCCCUCAGGGAUAUUUAAAACUUAUUUUAUAUACCAGUUAAUCUUAUUUAUCCUUAUAUUUUCUAAAUUGCCUAGCCGUCACACCCCAAGAUUGCCUUGAGCCUACUAGGCACCUUUGUGAGAAAGAAAAAAUAGAUGCCUCUUCUUCAAGAUGCAUUGUUUCUAUUGGUCAGGCAAUUGUCAUAAUAAACUUAUGUCAUUGAAAACGGUACCUGACUACCAUUUGCUGGAAAUUUGACAUGUGUGUGGCAUUAUCAAAAUGAAGAGGAGCAAGGAGUGAAGGAGUGGGGUUAUGAAUCUGCCAAAGGUGGUAUGAACCAACCCCUGGAAGCCAAAGCGGCCUCUCCAAGGUUAAAUUGAUUGCAGUUUGCAUAUUGCCUAAAUUUAAACUUUCUCAUUUGGUGGGGGUUCAAAAGAAGAAUCAGCUUGUGAAAAAUCAGGACUUGAAGAGAGCCGUCUAAGAAAUACCACGUGCUUUUUUUCUUUACCAUUUUGCUUUCCCAGCCUCCAAACAUAGUUAAUAGAAAUUUCCCUUCAAAGAACUGUCUGGGGAUGUGAUGCUUUGAAAAAUCUAAUCAGUGACUUAAGAGAGAUUUUCUUGUAUACAGGGAGAGUGAGAUAACUUAUUGUGAAGGGUUAGCUUUACUGUACAGGAUAGCAGGGAACUGGACAUCUCAGGGUAAAAGUCAGUACGGAUUUUAAUAGCCUGGGGAGGAAAACACAUUCUUUGCCACAGACAGGCAAAGCAACACAUGCUCAUCCUCCUGCCUAUGCUGAGAUACGCACUCAGCUCCAUGUCUUGUACACACAGAAACAUUGCUGGUUUCAAGAAAUGAGGUGAUCCUAUUAUCAAAUUCAAUCUGAUGUCAAAUAGCACUAAGAAGUUAUUGUGCCUUAUGAAAAAUAAUGAUCUCUGUCUAGAAAUACCAUAGACCAUAUAUAGUCUCACAUUGAUAAUUGAAACUAGAAGGGUCUAUAAUCAGCCUAUGCCAGGGCUUCAAUGGAAUAGUAUCCCCUUAUGUUUAGUUGAAAUGUCCCCUUAACUUGAUAUAAUGUGUUAUGCUUAUGGCGCUGUGGACAAUCUGAUUUUUCAUGUCAACUUUCCAGAUGAUUUGUAACUUCUCUGUGCCAAACCUUUUAUAAACAUAAAUUUUUGAGAUAUGUAUUUUAAAAUUGUAGCACAUGUUUCCCUGACAUUUUCAAUAGAGGAUACAACAUCACAGAAUCUUUCUGGAUGAUUCUGUGUUAUCAAGGAAUUGUACUGUGCUACAAUUAUCUCUAGAAUCUCCAGAAAGGUGGAGGGCUGUUCGCCCUUACACUAAAUGGUCUCAGUUGGAUUUUUUUUUCCUGUUUUCUAUUUCCUCUUAAGUACACCUUCAACUAUAUUCCCAUCCCUCUAUUUUAAUCUGUUAUGAAGGAAGGUAAAUAAAAAUGCUAAAUAGAAGAAAUUGUAGGUAAGGUAAGAGGAAUCAAGUUCUGAGUGGCUGCCAAGGCACUCACAGAAUCAUAAUCAUGGCUAAAUAUUUAUGGAGGGCCUACUGUGGACCAGGCACUGGGCUAAAUACUUACAUUUACAAGAAUCAUUCUGAGACAGAUAUUCAAUGAUAUCUGGCUUCACUACUCAGAAGAUUGUGUGUGUGUUUGUGUGUGUGUGUGUGUGUGUAUUUCACUUUUUGUUAUUGACCAUGUUCUGCAAAAUUGCAGUUACUCAGUGAGUGAUAUCCGAAAAAGUAAACGUUUAUGACUAUAGGUAAUAUUUAAGAAAAUGCAUGGUUCAUUUUUAAGUUUGGAAUUUUUAUCUAUAUUUCUCACAGAUGUGCAGUGCACAUGCAGGCCUAAGUAUAUGUUGUGUGUGUUGUUUGUCUUUGAUGUCAUGGUCCCCUCUCUUAGGUGCUCACUCGCUUUGGGUGCACCUGGCCUGCUCUUCCCAUGUUGGCCUCUGCAACCACACAGGGAUAUUUCUGCUAUGCACCAGCCUCACUCCACCUUCCUUCCAUCAAAAAUAUGUGUGUGUGUCUCAGUCCCUGUAAGUCAUGUCCUUCACAGGGAGAAUUAACCCUUCGAUAUACAUGGCAGAGUUUUGUGGGAAAAGAAUUGAAUGAAAAGUCAGGAGAUCAGAAUUUUAAAUUUGACUUAGCCACUAACUAGCCAUGUAACCUUGGGAAAGUCAUUUCCCAUUUCUGGGUCUUGCUUUUCUUUCUGUUAAAUGAGAGGAAUGUUAAAUAUCUAACAGUUUAGAAUCUUAUGCUUACAGUGUUAUCUGUGAAUGCACAUAUUAAAUGUCUAUGUUCUUGUUGCUAUGAGUCAAGGAGUGUAACCUUCUCCUUUACUAUGUUGAAUGUAUUUUUUUCUGGACAAGCUUACAUCUUCCUCAGCCAUCUUUGUGAGUCCUUCAAGAGCAGUUAUCAAUUGUUAGUUAGAUAUUUUCUAUUUAGAGAAUGCUUAAGGGAUUCCAAUCCCGAUCCAAAUCAUAAUUUGUUCUUAAGUAUACUGGGCAGGUCCCCUAUUUUAAGUCAUAAUUUUGUAUUUAGUGCUUUCCUGGCUCUCAGAGAGUAUUAAUAUUGAUAUUAAUAAUAUAGUUAAUAGUAAUAUUGCUAUUUACAUGGAAACAAAUAAAAGAUCUCAGAAUUCACUA